AUCCUCCUGGCAAGCUUCAAUAUAGCUGUGGAAGUCUGCAGUCUACAAGAGCCUACUAUAGACAUUCUACAACCAAGCAGAAUCAUGGAACAGCCGACUUCAAGCACCAAUGGGGAGAAGAGGAAGAGCCCCUGUGAAUCCAAUAACAAAAAAAAUGAUGAG